CUCAGCCCGAGUUAUGAGCACUUGCAUCUCUUCAAGGAACAGAAUCGCAUAGGCUAAGGAUGUGCAUCUCUUCCUUAUGUAUAUGUCUGUCUGUUGGCAGGGAGCAAACAUUUGUAGUAAAUGUGGUCUGGGAAUUUUCAGAUUCCCUUUUUGAGAGAAAACCAUGAGAAACAGGGUUUUCUACUGGUCACACUCUUCCCACAGGUACACUUGUUUAUGGGCCAAGAAGGAGGCCCAGCACACUCCUUCCGAGCUCCCACUUCCAGAGCCUUGUCCACCACCACCAGGGCAUCAUCUUCCCAGUGAUCUGUUCAUUCAUUCACUUAUUCAUUCAUUUAUUUAACAAUGUUCAGUGAUGGCUUACUGUGUGCCAGAAACUUUUCUAGGUGGUGGGGAUACAGACACAACGGACGUGAAUCCUGCCCUUGGGGGCCUUGCAUUGCUGGUGAGGGAAGUUAAAGAAAGUGACACAUUAGGAUGUCAUCUGAGGGCUAUGGGGAAAGGUUAAGCAGGGAAGGGGAUAAAGGAGGGCUCGGAGGGGUGGUCUGCAAUUUUAAAUAGGGUAGUCAGUGAAGGUGCCUAAAGAUAGAAAAGUGAUAAGGGAGUGAACUUCACAGAUAACUGGAGAAAGUGUUCUUGGUGGAGGAAACAGCAAGGGCAGAGACUCUGAGGAUGAAGCAUGGCAGGCACACUCCAGGAUGGUCAGCACUAAGCAAGGGGUGAGUGGAGAGCAACAUGAAACAGGAAGAGGGUAAGACCUUCUUGCUCUGAGUGAGAAGGAACAUCAAAUGGAGGGUUUGAGCAGAGGAGUGACAAGAUUGGACAUGCAUUUUAACAAGAGUACUCACUGUUAUGCAAAGAAUAUAUUUUAGGGAGUGUAUCAGCUAUCACUUGCUGCGUAACAACCCCAAAACUUAGCAGCUUCGAACAGCAAUGAUUAUGAUUUUUCAUGAUUCUGUGGCUUUGCCAGGCACUUCUUCUGCUGGCUUCACCUGGGCUGGCUUCUAAAACUGAAGUCAGCUGUAGGGUCAGGUGUGGCUGGAAGAUCCAAAUGACCCCGUACACAUUUGGCAGCUGGUGUUGGCUACUGAUACUGUACCUUAGCUCUCCACCAUGUGGUUCUAAUCCUGGUAGACCAGCUUUCUUACCUGGUAUGCAGAACUCUAAGAGAGUGAACAAGGGAGCAGCAAAGCCUCUAGAGGCUUAGGUUCGGGAACUCACACGUGGUUACUUCUGCCACAUGCUAUUGGUCAAAGCAAAUCACAAGGUCCGCCCACAUUCAAAAGGGUGGAGGAAUGUGCUCCACCUCUGGCUAGGAGGAAUAGCAAAGUUGCAUUGCAAAGGUGCAUGCAUAUUGCGAUGGGAGGAAUUUGUGGCCAUUAAACAGUCUAUCACAGGGACAAGGACAGAAGCAGGGAACAGGAGAAUAUAGCAGUAAUUCAGGGGAGAGCUGGUGGUGGCUUGAGCCAGGGUGGUGGGGACAAAAAUGUUGAGAAAGUUGGAUGCAGGAUAUAUUCCGAAGGUGGAACCAACAGGCCCACAUCAUUCAUUUCCAUCAUAAGAGCUCUUGACAUUGCUGUUCUGCUUUCAUUCAAUUCUAACUGCUUCCUCUCUCUCUCUCUCUCUCUCUCUCUCUCUCUCUCUCUCUCUCUCUCUCUCUCUCUCUCUCUUCCUUUCAUACACACAGGAGGCUCUGUCCUCCCCACCUUCUCUCCAUCCACACUUACUUCUCUGACAAUCCCAGCCACUCUCACACCUAGGGACCCUUAGCUGGAGCUCUCCAACCCAACAUCCUAAGUGAUGGCCUUACACCUCCCCCCCUUUGUCCACCUGUUCUACCUCAAGAUGAUGUUGAUAUUUCAGACUCAACAUUUUGAAGGCUGAAGUCAUUUACUCUUCUCCACAAGGUAUCGCAAAGGGUUUGAACUCCAGUCAUCCCUCUAUUCGGGAAUUAAUCUUGCAGUUUUGCUGAUUGUUGCUGGACAACAAUUUGAAACUUCCUUGGAACUAAGGAAAAUAGGUGUCCGGCUGAACAGUUUGUUGGGAAGAAAAGGGAGCUUGGAGAAAAUGAACAAUUACUGGGAUGUGGGUCAGUUCUUCAGCGUCAGCAUGCUGGCCCAUGAUGUCGGGAAAGCCGUCCAGGCAGCAGAGAGGUUGUUCAAACUGAAACCUCCAGUCUGGUACCUGCGAUCAUUAGUUCAGAACUUGUUACUAAUUCGGCGCUUCAAGAAAACCAUUAUUGAACACUCGCCCAGGCAAGAGCGGCUGAACUUCUGGUUAGAUAUAAUUUUUGAGGCAACAAAUGAAGUCACUAAUGGACUCAGAUUUCCAGUUCUGGUCAUAGAGCCAACCAAAGUGUACCAGCCUUCUUAUGUUUCCAUAAACAAUGAAGCCGAGGAGAGAACAGUUUCUUUAUGGCAUGUCUCACCCACAGAAAUGAAACAGAUGCACGAAUGGAAUUUUACAGCCUCUUCCAUAAAGGGAAUAAGCCUAUCAAAGUUUGAUGAAAGGUGUUGUUUUCUUUAUGUCCAUGAUAAUUCUGAUGACUUUCAAAUCUACUUUUCCACCGAAGAGCAGUGCAGUAGAUUUUUCUCUUUGGUCAAAGAGAUGAUAACCAAUACAGCAGGCAGUACGGUGGAGCUGGAGGGAGAGACCGAUGGAGACACCUUGGAGUAUGAGUAUGACCAUGAUGCAAAUGGUGAGAGAGUUGUCUUGGGGAAAGGCACGUAUGGGAUUGUGUAUGCUGGCCGAGAUCUGAGCAAUCAAGUGCGAAUAGCCAUCAAAGAAAUCCCGGAGAGAGAUAGCAGGUAUUCUCAGCCUCUGCACGAGGAGAUAGCCCUGCACAAGUACCUUAAGCACCGCAAUAUCGUUCAGUACCUGGGCUCUGUUUCAGAGAACGGCUACAUUAAGAUAUUUAUGGAGCAGGUGCCUGGAGGAAGCCUUUCUGCUCUUCUGCGAUCCAAAUGGGGGCCGAUGAAGGAACCGACAAUCAAGUUUUACACCAAACAGAUCCUGGAGGGCCUUAAGUAUCUUCAUGAAAACCAGAUCGUGCACAGAGACAUAAAGGGCGAUAAUGUUCUGGUGAACACCUACAGCGGAGUGGUGAAAAUCUCCGAUUUUGGAACCUCGAAACGUCUUGCGGGUGUGAACCCCUGCACAGAGACUUUUACUGGCACCCUGCAGUACAUGGCACCUGAGAUAAUUGACCAAGGGCCUCGCGGAUAUGGUGCCCCAGCCGAUAUCUGGUCCCUGGGCUGCACCAUCAUUGAGAUGGCCACCAGCAAGCCUCCGUUCCAUGAGCUUGGUGAGCCGCAGGCAGCCAUGUUCAAAGUGGGCAUGUUUAAGAUCCACCCUGAGAUUCCAGAAGCCCUUUCAGCUGAAGCCCGAGCCUUCAUUUUAUCCUGUUUCGAGCCUGACCCCCACAAACGUGCCACCACUGCUGAGCUACUGAGAGAGGGUUUCUUAAGGCAGGUGAACAAGGGCAAGAAGAACCGAAUUGCCUUCAAGCCCUCAGAAGGUCCCCGCGGUGUCGUCCUGGCCCUGCCCACACAGGGAGAGCCCAUGGCCACCAGCAGCAGCGAGCACGGCUCUGUCUCCCCAGACUCCGACGCCCAGCCUGACGCACUCUUUGAGAGGACCCGGGCGCCCAGGCACCACCUUGGCCACCUCCUCAGUGUUCCAGACGAGAGCUCAGCCUUGGAAGACCGGGGCUUGGCCUCGUCCCCGGAGGACAGGGACCAGGGCCUCUUCCUGCUACGCAAGGACAGUGAGCGCCGUGCCAUCCUGUACAAAAUCCUCUGGGAGGAGCAGAACCAGGUGGCUUCCAACCUGCAGGAGUGUGUGGCCCAGAGUUCCGAAGAGUUGCAUCUCUCAGUUGGACACAUCAAGCAAAUCAUUGGGAUCCUGAGGGACUUCAUCCGCUCCCCAGAGCACCGGGUGAUGGCGACCACAAUAUCAAAGCUCAAGGUGGACCUGGACUUUGACAGCUCGUCCAUCAGUCAGAUUCACCUGGUGCUGUUCGGAUUUCAGGAUGCCGUAAAUAAAAUUUUGAGGAACCACUUAAUUAGGCCCCACUGGAUGUUCGCGAUGGACAACAUCAUCCGCCGAGCGGUGCAGGCCGCGGUCACCAUUCUCAUCCCAGAGCUCCGAGCCCACUUUGAGCCUACCUGUGAGACUGAAGGGGUAGAUAAGGACAUGGAUGAAGCGGAAGAGGGCUAUCCCCCAGCCACCGGACCUGGCCAGGAGGCCCAGCCCCACCAGCAGCACCUGAGCCUCCAGCUGGGUGAGCUCAGACAGGAGACCAACAGACUUUUGGAACACCUAGUUGAAAAAGAGAGAGAGUACCAGAAUCUUCUGCGGCAAACUCUAGAACAGAAAACUCAAGAAUUGUAUCACCUUCAGUUAAAAUUAAAAUCGAAUUGUAUUACAGAGAACCCAGCAGGCCCCUACGGGCAGAGAACAGAUAAAGAGCUUAUAGACUGGUUGCGGCUGCAAGGAGCUGAUGCAAAGACAAUUGAAAAGAUUGUUGAAGAGGGUUAUACACUUUCGGAUAUUCUUAAUGAGAUCACUAAGGAAGAUCUAAGAUACCUUCGACUACGGGGUGGUCUCCUCUGCAGACUCUGGAGUGCGGUCUCCCAGUACAGAAGGGCUCAGGAGGCCUCAGAAACCAAAGACAAGGCUUGAUACCAAUCAGCUAAGCUGUGGCAGAGUGUCCCACCACGCUACAUGUUUUGUUAAAGCUUCUGUUAGUGUAUACACGAAUUCCGCUGUGUUUACAUAUUUAAAAAUGCCAUUGUUCAAUUAAUAGUUUAAGAACUUGUUUUAAAUACUGUCCUGAGUUUCUUUUGAAACCUGUUAUUUAUAAACAUAGAACUGUGUGUAUUGUGAAAACAGUGAGCCUUGGUUUUGACCUCCCGGAAUAUUAGGAAAUUCACUUGUAGUCCCAGCUAUGCAGGAGGCUGAGGUGGGAGGAUUGCUUGAGCCCAGGAGGUGUGGAGGCUGCAGUGAGCCAUGAUCACACCACUGCACUCCAGCCUGGGCAACAGAGCCCGACCCUGUCUCAAAAAAAGUACACCCUUCAGCACUUGCUGGAAUGGUGAAACAAACAAGGGGUAUUUAACAAACAUGGAAGCUGGGACACUGCCUCAGAACUGGUAUGGUACUUCAAUUUGAGAAACACAAAACUGAUACGAAUGUGCCUUGUAGUUAAUGUUUGAUAUGAACAGAAAAUAGCUUCAUAUUUAUACUGAAUGUGUAAGUAGAGAAAACUAAGUUAUGUGGCCUUUGAAAUGAUUACAAAAUUGGAAUGAUUACAAAAGUCUUAUUUUAAAAUGGAACUGUCCUCUUGCCUGAUAAUAAAUAUUGUAUCUUGUA